AUGCCUCCAAUAUGGCGUCCUCCACAUAGGCAGUGGCUGUGGUUUCUACCCCGGGUGGCCGGGGGCAGUGCUGAGCUGGGACUGUUGUUUGCCCAGCCUGGGCUGCAGAAAGCAGCAGUUAAAGUUCGUUUCUGGUCACUGCUCCAGGAAGCCACCUUACUCUGAGGGUCAAGAAUUGCCGCUUCCUUUUAGUUACUGUAAGUUCCUCCUCUGCCCCUGGUUUGUUUCCCGCGGCACUUCUGGAUACCCCCAGGUCCCAGACCCUUCCAGACUCAAACCAUGAACUUUCGGCAGCUGCUGUUGCACUUGCCACGUUAUCUUGGAGCCUCGGGUUCCCCGCGUCGCCUGUGGUGGUCCCCGUCCCUCGACACCAUCUCCUCGGUGGGCUCUUGGCGUGGUCGGUCCUCCAAGUCCCCGGCCCACUGGAAUCAGGUAGUGUCAGAGGCGGAGAAGAUCGUGGGGUACCCCACGUCCUUCAUGAGCCUUCGCUGCCUGCUGAGCGACGAGCUCAGCAACAUCGCUAUGCAGGUGCGGAAGCUGGUGGGCACUCAGCACCCUCUGCUUACCACAGCCAGGGGGCUUGUACAUGACAGCUGGAAUAGCCUCCAGUUGAGGGGCUUGGUGGUGCUCCUUAUCUCUAAAGCAGCUGGGCCCAGCAGCGUGAACACUUCAUGUCAGAACUAUGACAUGGUCAGUGGGAUCUACUCAUGUCAAAGAAGUUUGGCAGAGAUCACGGAGCUAAUUCAUAUUGCUCUCCUUGUACAUCGUGGGAUAGUAAAUUUAAAUGAGUUGCAAUCAUCUGAUGGUCCACUGAAAGACAUGCAAUUUGGAAAUAAAAUUGCUAUCCUGAGUGGAGACUUUCUUCUAGCAAAUGCCUGCAAUGGACUAGCUCUGCUACAGAACACCAAGGUUGUGGAACUUUUAGCAAGUGCUCUUAUGGACUUGGUACAAGGAGUAUAUCAUGAAAAUUCUACUUCAAAGGAAAGUUAUAUCACAGAUGAUAUUGGAAUAUCGACUUGGAAGGAGCAGACUUUUCUCUCCCAUGGUGCCUUACUAGCAAAGAGCUGCCAAGCUGCAAUGGAAUUAGCAAAGCAUGAUGCUGAGGUUCAGAAUAUGGCAUUUCAGUAUGGGAAGCACAUGGCCAUGAGUCAUAAGAUAAAUUCUGAUGUCCAGCCUUUUAUUAAAGAAAAGACCAGUGACUCCAUGACUUUUAAUCUAAACUCAGCUCCUGUAGUCUUACAUCAGGAAUUUCUUGGAAGAGAUUUGUGGAUUAAACAGAUCGGAGAGGCUCAAGAAAAAGGAAGAUUGGACUAUGCUAAGGAACGAGGUCUCGCUGUUACCCAGACUGGUGAUGCUUUUUUUAUGACUCAAAGAAUGCCUCUGGGGUUUCUUAUCACAGAAGCACUUGACAAUGGAAGAGAUUUCCACUGGAAAAUGGCAAAGAGAAAAAUAUGGUGCACAAAUAAGAGCACCCCUGGACCAAGCAAUGGCUCUGCCACCAACUCAAUGCAAAAUCUGUUGCGAGAAAGAAUCAAAGCUGGCAAAGGUGUGACUUCAGCUAUUGACCUGUGUCGUUACCAUGGAAACAAGGCACUGGAGGCCCUGGAGAGCUUUCCUCCCUCGGAGGCCAGAUCUGCUUUAGAAAACAUUGUGUUUGCUGUGACCAGAUUUUCAUGACAUCAAAUUAAAAAGACACUAUUGUUAGUUAGCUGAAAAUCCUAGGGAAUGAGGUUGAUUGGGAGCGCUUUCACGAUGCGUUAAUGACUUUUAAAACAUAUGCAUUUUUCCUUCCUUUUAUCACAUUGCUAAAUGAGUUCUGCUUUCUUUUUGGAACUGCUACAAACAAAAUUAGAAGAAAAAAAGGUCAAGCAGUUUUCACUUGUCACGCCAGAAGCACACUUGAGGCUGCAGUCGCAGAAAUAAUUAAUGAGAUUCGCUCCUGUGACCUCAGCAAAUGGACAGGAAAUAAGUCCUUAUUGAUUGGACCGAGCCAGGGAUGGCGCCAGGGCGGUGGCCUGUGGUUUUUCCUGCUAGAGAGGACAAAGCAAGUUGGAAGCUGCAGGUGUCAAGAGAAAUGCUCUCAAUACCAACCAGGGAGGAUUGUCUAAUCAAAAACUAGUGACCAAUUUGUCAUAAUGGAGAGUAGUUCAAUGGAUUGAGAAAAAUAUGUUUUAUUUGUUGGCUUGUAAUUAUGUCUCUGGAUUAUUAUUAUUUUUUUUUUAGAUGUAGUUUUGCUCUUGUUGCCCAGGCUGGAGUGCAAUGGUGCAGUUUUGACUCACUGCAACCUCCGCCUCCUGGGUUCAAGUGAUUCUCCUGCCUCAGCCUCCCGAGUAGCUGGAAUUACAGGCACCUGCCACCACGCCUGGCUAAUUUUGUAUUUUUAGUAGAGAUGGGGUUUCACUAUGUUGGUCAGGCUAGUCUCGAACUCCUGACCUCAGGUGAUCCGCCUGCCUCGGCCUCCCAAAGUGCUGGGAUUAGAGGCUUGAGCCACUGCACCUGGCCUCAUGUCUCUGGAUUUAUAAUGCAGUAUGAAUAUACUUUGUGCUUUAUGGUUUUUAUAAUGUCUUUUUGGAGAAAUUGCCGAAAAGUUGCCAAAUACUUGAAGUAGGAGAUUAAAAUGUUAUCAAAUGUUAAAUUGGUUAUAUUAGGAAUAGUCUGUUUUUCUUUCCUGAAGAUCAGUUUUUUUAUUCAAACACAUUUCAAAGAACCAAAUUUUUUUUUUCUUUAAGGAAAAAGGAGCUUUUUUUCAAGUGAAAUGUAUUCAUUUGUAAUACUUUGGUUUAAGGCAUACUUUAAUUUUUACGAGUUUCAGAAACAGAAUUUUUGUACUAGGGAAUUCAUUGGUGAGAGUGUUCUUUUAACCUCAGAAUGUCAAAUUUUGGUCUUGAACCACAGACAUCCAAUUACAGAAAGAAUAUAAGCAAUCUCACAGGCCUGCAAUCGGACACUGUCUCUGUGUGGUUCAUAGGAGAUGAUUUUUGAGGUUUGCACUCAUGCAAUUUGAGAACACCGUUGACAAGAAGGCUGAGUUUACAUAAAUGAUCUAGAUUGAAACUCAGCUACCUUUCUUCCUCAUGUGGUGUAAUUACAGCCCUAUCUGGAGACAGCGAAUACAGCAAACAGAUUUUAUUACCUAGUUCGCUCAAACACUACAUGAAGUUAUUUUAGUUAAAGCCCUCCCCCAAAAGUUAUAAAACCAUUUUAUCAGGGCCCAACAUGUGGCAUGCAAUGAAGAGAAAAUGUAAAGCUACAGAGGUUAAUGUAUUGUAUUAUAAAAUAUUUUAAGUGUACUCAAAAUAUCAUAAUUGUACAGUUUAUGCCACCAUAAUUUGAGGCCUAUAGAUUUAGCUUAAGAGAACACUGUUCUGUUUGAAAUGCUUUCUGUCACUGAAAUUGGCUUAAUUAGUAACCAUGGAUAAGAUGCUUUAGAUCAGACUAGGUUUUAAUCAUUAACUUCCACAAAGAAGUCAUACUUUGCGUUAGGUGUGCUGGUUGGAUGUGCAGGAACUUCAGCAAGCAGUAGGUUUUACUAAGCAGAUGGUCGGGCACUGCAGGGCACCAGGCAGGAUCCUAGGGCGCCUCUUAUUCUGCGUUAGCAUCUGGUUUGCUGUAUGACCUUGCACAAGUCACUUCCUUCUGAGCCUCAAUUUUCUCAUCUGUACAAUGAGAUUCAAAAGUUGACCUGAAAGUCAAGUGUGAAAAAAAAAAAGAGAUUAAACAAGAUAAUUAUGAAA